AGAAAAAAAAGGUGAGAGGUGACUGUUUUGCUUUUUUCUGAACAUAUCAGACCAAACCUGGGCUGUUUAGCCAUUUUUUUUUUUUUUUUUUUUUUUUUUUUGCGAUGGUGUCUCGCUCUGUCACCCAGGCUGGAGUGCAGUGAUGCAAUCUCGGCUCACUGCAACCUCUGCCUUCCAGGUUCAAGCGAUUCUCCUGCCUCGGCCUCCUAAGUAGCUGGGAUUACAGAUGUGCACCCCCACGCCCAGCUCAUUUUUUCUGUAUUUUUAGUAGAGACGGAUUUAAACAUGUUGGACAGGCUGGUCUCGAACUUCUGACCUCUGGUGAUCUGUCUGCCUCUGCUUCUUAAAGUGGUAGGAUUACAGGCAUGAGCCACCGCGCCUGGUUUGCCAAUUUUUUGACAACAUAUCAACAUCAUUUACGAUGGGCAUGGCCUCAGUGUAGUGUGUCUAGACAAGGUGGCCGGAAGAGAGAGGAAUAUGCAAACCAGGCUUGAAGAUGGGUUAAAUCAGAGAUUUUCAUUCCACAAAAGAGAAAUUUUAAUGGGGUCAGAACAUUGAUCUUCUAAUAUUUGAAAGCCUGUUAACUAGGAGAGAGAGAGCAAACGAUUUUGUUGUAGAAGGACCCACCCAGCUCUGACGGUUUAAAGCAUCAUGAAUGCGAAUUUGAACUCCAGAAAAGCAGAGCUUCCUAACAAUGGGACUUCCACAGCAAUGGGAUCUGCUUCCUCUUUCAGUGUGUGCCUUUUCUAUGAGCGAGAGACUCCUAGGAAAGCAGCAGCCCAUUAGGAAAACGUGUGGGAACUCACUCGCAGGUUCUUUAUUUUUUUUGAGAUGGAGUUUUGCUCGUUGCCCAGACUGGAGCACAAUGGUGCGAUCUUGGCUCCCUGCAACCUGCGCACCAUGAGUUCAAGUGAUUCUCCAGCUCCCUCUCCUGAGUAGCUGCGAUUACAGGCAUCCACCACCAUGCCUGGCUAAUUUUUUGUAUUUUUAGUAGAGAUGGGGUUUCACCAUGUUGUCCAAGCUGGUCUCAAACUCCUGACGUCAAGUGAUCCACCCACUUUGGCCUCCCAAAGUGCUGGGAUUACAGGCAUGAGCCACUGAGCCCAGCCGGGAACCCACAGGUUUUUUGGAUGGUCUCUGAAUGUCAUGUAACUCUUUUAUUUUUUAUCAAAAAAAAUUUUUUUGACACAAUAUCUUGCUGUGUUGCCCAGACGGGAGUGCAGUGGCAAGAUCAUGGCUCACUGCAGCUUCUAACUCCUGGGCUCAAGUGAUCUUCCUGUCACGAGUCUCCCAAGUAGUUGGAACACAGGUGCCAGCCACCACACCUGGCUAAUUUGGUUUGGUUUUGUUUUUUUAGAGAUGGGCUCUUACUAUGUUGCCUAUACUGGUCUUGAACUGCUGGCCUCAGGCAAUCUUCCUCCCUUGGCCACCCAAAGUGCUGGGAUUACAAGCAUGAGCCACUGUGCACAGCUGAAAUUUUCGACUUAGUCUUUUUGUACAUGUGAUAUUUUAUUCAUAGAAUCCAUAAAUGGAAGGGAAAUUUCUGAGUUCAGAGCAAUACAUAUGAUACAAAACUUGAUAUAUAGACUAGAGUUUCUUAGCCGAACUGGAGGGGCUGGCUUAGGUAAUCCAUGGAUUCCCUGAAAUUGGGGACACCAUUGGAAAUAUGUGUGAGCUCAGGGGCAGUUUCCUAUGAUUUUUAGGCCUCAAAAUGUCUCUUGGACUCAAAAUUGCCUUAGGGCAGAGGACGUGUGUACCCCCAGUAUAGAAUCUCGGACAGUGAAUGUGAGUAAACAUUCGGCAGAAAAGCUCUGCCAAACUGAGUGCUCUGAUGUGACUUUUUCAUCAAGUCAGUAUUCCUGGGAUCUCUUGUACAUGAUAAUCUCACUCUUGUACAUGAUAAUCUCACUCUUGUACAUGAUAAUCUCACUCUUAUAAGGUUUCAUCGUUUCUGCUUACCCUAGUUUUCUUUCCCACUCUGUUCCCUCUCCCACCAGACUGGACUCUGAAAUGGGCAUGUACAGAGACAAAGAGACCCCAACAUGCUUCAGGCUUUGAGUGGAGAGGACACAGCCUCUGCUGGGACAGGGAACAGAGGGAUGUGGAGUCCCUGAAGAUGCUUUUGGACAAUGGUCUGAGGUUGGGACAGUGGCAGGAGAUACCAUUCACCCAGGAUCUCCAGGACAAGAGAUCAGCCUGGCAGUUACAUGUGUUUUUUUUCAAACUGGUUGCCAGGUUGGCAUGAGCGAUGACAUCAGAGAUUCCGACCAUCCUGAUUGGAGGGACCGGACUCCGUGGUGCCUGGAGAUCAGUUGGACAACAGUAUCUUCUCAGAGCUGUUCUCCACUCCUGACUUCUCCUAGGCUUGAGAAUUGAUAACAUACUCUUCUGGAUCCUAGCAGUGAUCAGAAGAAGGCCAUGGACAGAACGGAGACUAGGUUCCGUAAGAGGGGACAGAUUACGGAAAAGAUCACGACCAGCCGUCAACCGCAACCCCAGAAUGAGCAGAGUCCCCAGCGGAGCACCUCGGGGUACCCCCUCCAGGAGGUGGUGGAUGAUGAAGUGUUGGGACCAUCAGCCCCUGGGGUAGAUCCCAGCCCCCCAUGUAGGUCCCUUGGCUGGAAAAGGAAGAGGGAGUGGUCAGAUGAAUCUGCGGAGGAGCCGGAGAAGGAGCUCGCCCCUGAACCUGAGGAGACCUGGGUAGUGGAGAUGCUGUGUGGGCUCAAGAUGAAGCUGAAGCAACAGCGAGUGUCACCCAUCCUCCCUGAGCACCACAAGGGCUUCAACAGUCAGCUUGCCCCUGGGGUAGAUCCCAGCCCCCCGCAUAGGUCCUUUUGCUGGAAAAGGAAGAUGGAGUGGUGGGACGAAUCUGAGGAGUCGUUGGAGGAGGAGCCACGGAAGGUGCUCGCCCCUGAGCCUGAGGAGAUCUGGGUGGCGGAGAUGCUGUGUGGCCUCAAGAUGAAGCUGAAGCGACGGCGAGUGUCGCUCGUGCUCCCUGAGCACCACGAGGCCUUCAACAGGCUGCUUGAGGAUCCUGUCAUUAAAAGAUUCCUGGCCUGGGACAAAGAUCUGAGGGUGUCGGACAAGUAUCUCCUGGCUAUGGUCAUAGCGUAUUUCAGCCGGGCCGGCUUCCCCUCCUGGCAAUACCAACGCAUUCAUUUCUUCCUGGCUCUCUACCUGGCCAAUGACAUGGAGGAGGACGACGAGGACUCCAAACAAAACAUCUUCCACUUCCUGUAUGGGAAGAACCGCUCUCGCAUACCCUUGCUCCGUAAGCGUUGGUUCCAGUUAGGCCGUUCCAUGAACCCGAGGGCCAGGAAGAAGCGCUCUCGCAUACCCUUGCUCCGUAAGCGUCGGUUCCAGUUAGGCCGUUCCAUGAACCCGAGGGCCAGGAAGAACCGCUCUCGCAUACCCUUGCUCCGUAAGCGUCGGUUCCAGUUAGGCCGUUCCAUGAACCUGAGGGCCAGGAAGAACCGCUCUCAGAUAGUCCUGUUCCAGAAACGUCGGUUCCAGUUCUUCUGUUCCAUGAGCGGCAGGGCUUGGGUUUCCCCGGAGGAGUUGGAGGAGAUCCAGGCUUAUGACCCAGAGCACUGGGUGUGGGCGCGAGAUCGCGCUCACCUUUCCUAGAGCUCCAGGGACCGUGGAGGCCUGAGGUCAUCGGCCUGAGAGAAGAACACCGGACCCAGGGGAGAUGUGGAUUUUCAGCAGGAACUUUAUUCCAAUGCUAAUGGCAGACACCAGGAAGGAGGAGAGGAACCAUUUGUGCAGAUCAUCUAGAAGAACCUGGACCAUUCUUGAUGGAGCUGAAUACAGUGAUCACGUUGUCCUCCUAGGAGCAGGGGUGGGGGGAGGGGGGUGGGGUCCUUCUAGGAG